GGAAGCGGAAGCCAGCACGCAGGGCGGUGGGGUGCAGCGGCGGCGGUCUCGGCGUGCCAGGCCCAGGGCGCCCCGCGGGGGCGUGCGCGCCACACGCGUGCGGGGCAGGCUGGGCGCCGGGCGGCACCCUCCCAGCCCCGGCGUCUAUUUACCAACAAACUGCCGGCGCUCAGCAGCGGCGCAUUCCGACGCGCUGACUAAGCGGUUGGCGCUGGCGGUCUGCACUUGACUCCCCUUCAGGUCCACCGCGGCUGGACCAGAAUCGACGUGCAGAUCCCCGAAAUCGGGAGACUGCAAAUGCAGAUUCCCUGCGUCUCCGCAGCCCCCGGGCCUCUGCCCACCACCCAGCUCCCUGUCUCUUGGGCAUCCAGUCUCGCCACCUCUCUAGCAUUUCUGCCAUUAUAACCGAGGUUCCUGGACUGCACCAAUCGCUCUGCAACCCCAGCACCUCUCGGAGGAGACCCCGAGGCCGUAUGGCCACCUCCUGUCUUACCCCUACACCGAGCCAGCGAACCCCGGAGACUCCUACCUGUCCUGCCAGCAACCCGCGGCGCUCUCUCAGCCCCUCUGCGGACCUGCAGAGCACCCUCAGGAACUCGAGGCAGGUAAGUUCGGCCGUGGAGGCUCUUCCCACCUCUGGGGUUCGGCUCCUGUGCGCCCCUAAACUUCUCCCUCGCCUGGUUGGACGCAGCUAGCGGGAUUCAAACCUUCCUUGGAUUCCCUGGGAUGUGGGGGUGGGGGGAGGGCGAAGGGAUGGGGCGGGAGACACGGGGGGAGGGGCGGGGGAGAGUUGAUCUAGGUCUCCUUUCAAAACCGACCUGGUUUCGAUUUGCAGUUGUGUAAAGACAGGCGAGAGGGCCCCCCCAACCCCCCACCUGGAGCAGCGGGGCUGUCUGUACCUACUAGUAACGGAAAACUGAAGCAAUCCAGAUGUGGGGAUGGGGGCCUAGCCCCUUUGUCAGAAUCCCCCAGCCCCCGUCCUGUACUCCCUUCCUGCCCCAUUGUCGCCCCUCUCUGCGUUAGUCUUGUCUCAGAAAGCAGUGAUCAAGCCAAACACUGAAAAACAGAUCAAGUCCUGGUAGGAGGGCUGUAGACAUCGAGGCUUAUUCUGGGCUCUGUCCUCUCCCUUCCCUGGCCUUACCCGCUCUCCUCAGACCAGGCCUGACCUUGACUGGAAGCUGGCCUGGCAGAAUCUGGGAGUAGGACCCUUCUAUCCAUUGUUCUGAGAAGGUAGCCAAAGGCUGGUAGGAAAGUCGCUCAUCUCUCCCUGACUACCUCAGCCUUCCAGCCAAAGGAGCCGGCCAUCGCUGUCAUCUCCACUCUUUGGCUUUGGGGUAGGUUAGGCCACAGUUCCCGUUGCCUGGAGCAACUCUGAGCUCCUGAGAAAGUGCUCACUGGAAGGCCUCAAUGAAGCGGAGAACCUGGCCCGUCUUUGGGAUCCUGGGCCUUGCAGCUGAGCUGACAUACAAUGUGGGUAUGGCAUUGCCCACAAUCCCAUCUGCACUGGCUCCAGCUUAGCCUCCAGGUCUCUGGACUCUCUGCCUCCAUCUAAUUGCUCACCCCCUCCUCCUGCAAUUGUCUUUGGCAGUCUCUUCCAAGGAGGCACACCCAUUAGGUGACUUCACUGGAGUCAGCUCAGGACCAAGACAUCUUCCUCCCUUCUCCUGUGGCUCUGACAUGCUCACAAACCAUCAGAGCCAGAAGUGACCCUAGGAUUUAGAAGCUCAACUUCUUUGAUGUAUAGAUGGGUAAAGCAUGUGGCCAGGAGCAUCGAUUUUAGGGAGCUUCCUCCAACCCCCCCAAAAUUAACUGCCUUCUGUGACAGAACUGUGGCUGUCUCCUGGGCUGCGGAGUGUGGCUGGAGUGGGCGCAGUUGCAGGGAGGAGUAGUUCUAGUUUUUCAAAUGAAUCCCUUUGACUGUCCUUUAGUGUAUGCUAAUAGGAUAUGUUUGUGUGUGUUAUGUGUUUGGGGACUGGGGUGGGAAUAUCAUGACCUUGUCCUCAGGGGAAUUGCUGGCAGUAGGGUUGGUGUUGUCAGUCUUGUCUGAGAUCUAAGGACAACAGAGUGGAGAGUUCAUUUUCUUUAAGGACUUUCCCCCAUCCAGCGAAAAACCACACACACCCAGAUUUCCUUAGAAUACAUUUCUAGCAUUUCUCUGCUGGAACUGGUGGGUUUGGGCGCUCUAGAGUGGAGGGCAUGUGAUCGAGAGCUUGGGGUCCUCCUUUUACUUCCACUCUAUGUCCACUCCUGCCUUGGGAAAAGGUUUGGCUCCAAGUGAGCGGUGCCACCACCCCGUUGAGCCGUAGGGAGCAGCGGGCCUGGAGGGAGGCCUUGGGGCUCCAUGAUCGCGACCCGGGCAGAUCUCGUAACUUGCUGGAACUGGGGUAGGGAAAGGCAGCUGUCCGGGAAGGAACUUGGAGGGGGUCUGCUGGGAGAGUUGGGGCGCGGAGGGCUAUGCGAAUUCAGCAACCGGGUCGGCCUCAGAGACUCUGCGUCCCCGCUCGAAUUGCGCAGUCCACGCAGCCAGAGAGGCGCGGGUGGGCUCUGGGCUGCCAGCCCAGAGCUGCCAGCAGUGGGGUCGAGGCAGGGGAGGCAGGACAGGCGCGGGCGGGAGCGGAAACCCAACGGUUUUUCUGGGAAUUGGUUGAGGCAGGGUCGAGGAGGGAGGAUCUCAGAAGCCCGCAGCGCCCGAGGCCACGGGUGAGGGAUGCGGGGGAGGUGACGGCAGCUGGUGACCGCGGCUGGCCGAGGGCGGGUACACUGACGUGUGGAGGGUGAGCCCGACUAGGGGAAGAAGGUGGGGGGACGCGGGCGGACAGAAGCCGCUCUCUCUCGGCUCAGGUCGGCUGGACAGACCCGCAGGGAAUGCGGCGAACGCUGCCCUAAGCGCCCGGGCAUUGCGGCUGCUCCAUCCGCCCUACUCCUCCCAUUGCCUGGGACCUCUGCAGCGUCCCCGUAGAGCCGCGCAGGUUAGGGUGGCUGGCUUGGAAGAACAGAAACCCCUCGGCCCAACCCUCCCCUGUCCCUCAGCAUUCUAGGGCUGGGCUGUCCCGCGGCCGAGAUUCCUGGAGAGCUAGGCGGGCCAGAGCUGACCAGAUCCCCCGCGGCGGCACCGCAGCGCGAUCCAGGAGUGGCCCCGCCGGGCUACGCUGCGCGCUCUUGGAACCCGGGUCACCUUCCCUGCCGCCGGAACCGCUCUGUGCGCGCUGCCCAACGAAGGAAGGGGCUGCCCCACGCAGACCCGGCUUCUGGGGGUCCCUGGAAACCCAGGCGGCCACGGUGUGGCGGGGGAGACAUGGUCACUUUUCCUGCAGGGUGCGCCUGAGCAGAGGGGCAGCCCGUUACAGUAGGCGAGGCCAGGGCAAACCCGGGGUCACUAUCAGCGCUGCGAGACUGGUAUUCAAGGUCCUCUCAGCCGGGCCUCUCACCCACCCCGCUGGCCGCAGCCGGAGGCUGCCACGCGGACACCGUCUCAAGCCUCUGAGCAUUGCUCUGAGCCUCUGCCUGCAAUGUCCUUCCUCUGUCAUCUCUAGGCCUCGGCUCAGCCCUGGACCUAGCCUUUCUGCCCCGCCCUACCCCAAGCUGGCGCCACCGCCCGUGGCUGAACUCCGACCUCCCACCGCAGGCGCCGCGGUACCCUGGCUGUGGCCCUCGGCGCUUUCUUCCUAGGGUCACAGGACCCAUACGAGUGGGAGCUCCCUGGGAGCAGAACUGCGUCUUGUAUCACCUGGCGCGGUGAACGUGGGGGUUGAAACGCUCCACGCGGAAGGUAGAGGGCAGGGGCCAAGGGGGCGAUCCUGGUGGCUGCGCUUUUUGCUAUUUGCUGCCGACGGCAUGCAGACGAGAUGCAAAUAAGCUUAUGAAACUGUCCGUCCUACCCCCUCGCUCCCUCCUCGCCCCCUACACCGUGUUGUGCUGCCCACCAGACUCGGAGAAGCCGCGGCUGUCCCCGGAACCCUCCGAGCGGCGCCCUCAGGCCCCCGCCAAAAAGCUCCGCAAGCCGAGGACCAUCUACUCCAGCCUGCAGCUGCAGCACCUAAACCAGCGUUUCCAGCACACGCAGUACCUGGCGCUGCCCGAGAGGGCCCAGCUGGCAGCGCAGCUCGGCCUCACCCAGACCCAGGUAAAGAUCUGGUUUCAGAACAAACGCUCCAAGUAUAAGAAGCUCCUGAAGCAGAAUUCUGGGGGGCAGGAAGGGGACUUCCCUGGGAGGACCUUCUCUGUGUCUCCCUGCUCCCCACCCCUCCCCUCCCUCUGGGAUCUACCCAAGGCAGGGACCCUGCCCACCAGUGGCUAUGGCAACAGCUUUGGAGCCUGGUAUCAGCAUCACUCCUCAGAUGUCCUGGCUUCGCCUCAGAUGAUGUGAAUCUGGGGAAGGGCGGGUCAGGCCCACAGCCUUCCUGCAAAGCCCAGGACCCAGGCAGUCCACCUGCACCCCUUCUGGGCUGGGAGGAAACCAGCUCCAGAUGGGUUUUCUCUGGAGGACAAGCAGUUAGAGGAGAAAAAGGAAUGGAGCAGAGCCUGUACCCCUAACCCUAACAGCUAAAUCAAGGACCUCAGCCUUAUAUAAUCAUUGUCCCCACCACUACCAUGGACUGGACACCUUCACUCCAGCUGGACAAAGACUCUGGAGAGAGAGCCAUUGGCUGGAGUUGAGACUGUCCCCAGAACCCUUGGUCUUGCCACUCCCCCACUCCUUCUUCCCUCUCUCCCUUUCUCCUCUCCCUGCUUUCUUGAAAAGGACUGAAUCGCCACUACAGCCUGGGUGCAAAAUCAGCAAGAAACAUUGAGUAUUUUUUUUUCUUUGUAUGCCUUUGGCCUUGCACAACCCAUUUGUGAGCAAAAGCAGAAGUGGACCACCAUCAGCUCCCACCCACCCAGCGAUUUUUCCUUGGAGGUCAGCCCGUUACCCCCAUAACUGAUUUACCUACUUACCAUACUGGGAGGUAGAAGAGAUGCAGAGAAAUGUGGAAUUUGUGGACCUAUGGGUAAUUUAUGCUUUCCUCCUAAAAAAAAAAAAAAAGCCCUCUUUCCCACCCCCUCCCCAUCUCCCCUUUUUGAAUAGAUAAUGGAUCCAAUUAUCCAUAUAAUUCAAUAGGUAUUUAUUGAGAGGCUCCCUUCUAUUCCCCAUCCCUAAUCCCUAACGAACCCACGGGCACACACUUUUGGAAACCUGGUAAAGUAACACUUAGGGGGAAAUGGGGACAAACUGGCUCUCUGGAUUAGUGCGGGUAUAGACACCCCCAAAUAGGUGGGUAGGCCCAUUGAUUCAGCUCCUUGCAGCUGUCUCUGUUCAAAGGAACUGUGCAGAUUUAGAACGAAUUGGAGCUUGAGCUUCACACCACCAGCUUCCAGAGAUUAAAGUUUGUACAAAACAUUGCA